AGAGGAGCAGGAACUGGAACCCUGGCCGAGUCCGAAAAAAGCCAGAUCUGGAAGGUGGCUGCGGAACGGUUUUAAGCGGAAGAUGGAGGAGCCGGAGGAACCGGCGGACAGUGGGCAGUCGCUGGUCCCGGUUUAUAUCUAUAGUCCCGAGUAUGUCAGUAUGUGUGACUCCCUGGCCAAGAUCCCCAAACGGGCCAGUAUGGUGCAUUCUUUGAUUGAAGCAUAUGCACUGCAUAAGCAGAUGAGGAUAGUUAAGCCUAAAGUGGCCUCCAUGGAGGAGAUGGCCACCUUCCACACUGAUGCUUAUCUGCAGCAUCUCCAGAAGGUCAGCCAAGAGGGCGAUGAUGAUCAUCCGGACUCCAUAGAAUAUGGGCUAGGUUAUGACUGCCCAGCCACUGAAGGGAUAUUUGACUAUGCAGCAGCUAUAGGAGGGGCUACGAUCACAGCUGCCCAAUGCCUGAUUGACGGAAUGUGCAAAGUAGCAAUUAACUGGUCUGGAGGGUGGCAUCAUGCAAAGAAAGAUGAAGCAUCUGGUUUUUGUUAUCUCAAUGAUGCUGUCCUGGGAAUAUUACGAUUGCGACGGAAAUUUGAGCGUAUUCUCUACGUGGAUUUGGAUCUGCACCAUGGAGAUGGUGUAGAAGACGCAUUCAGUUUCACCUCCAAAGUCAUGACCGUGUCCCUGCACAAAUUCUCCCCAGGAUUUUUCCCAGGAACAGGUGACGUGUCUGAUGUUGGCCUAGGGAAGGGACGGUACUACAGUGUAAAUGUGCCCAUUCAGGAUGGCAUACAAGAUGAAAAAUAUUACCAGAUCUGUGAAAGUGUACUAAAGGAAGUAUACCAAGCCUUUAAUCCCAAAGCAGUGGUCUUACAGCUGGGAGCUGACACAAUAGCUGGGGAUCCCAUGUGCUCCUUUAACAUGACUCCAGUGGGAAUUGGCAAGUGUCUUAAGUACAUCCUUCAAUGGCAGUUGGCAACACUCAUUUUGGGAGGAGACAGGAGGCUAUAACCUUGCCAACACGGCUCGAUGCUGGACAUACUUGACCGGGGUCAUCCUAGGGAAAACACUAUCCUCUGAGAUCCCAGAUCAUGAGGUAAGUAAGGCUCUGACAAGUCCUCUCUUCUUUAAGGGGAAGAGCUGAGUCAUUCCACCUAAUCAAAAUCACGUCCUCACCACUCAAUACCGUUUUGUUGAGAGACACUUCAAUAACAAUAACACACUGUCUUGGCAGAAUAGUGGACUCUUGUUCCAAAAUAUCCAAGACCUUCUGCCUUUUUGUUUUUUUACAAGAGAUCUCAAAGGCCAACCAACUUUAAUUUCUCAAUUAAUUACAGAGACUGUGGGAAGGGGUCACCUGUUCACACAAAGAAUUCUUUGGAAUAUGUGCAUAUUUUUAUCCCCUAGCCUCAAAAAGGAAGGGGCUAUUUUUAAAAUGUGUAAGCUGGAUUCUCAUCUUUUUUUUAAGAAGUUUCAUAGGUGGUACGUGGCACAUGUUCUUUGGUGGUAGUCCUGAUCUCUCAAUUUUCUUUGACUAAUGUAAAAUUCAAGAAACCCACAAGCACUACAAAGACCAUUGCUGAUGUUUUUCUAGCAAUUAGUGGCACACAGAGGCUGGAAUAGGACCAUCCAAAAUGUGAAACGUCAUUUGAGCCCUUGCCAUUUUCUUUAGUCAUACAAGAUGGGCUUUAUGUUUUCCAAAGCAAAGAUGUCUGUUCUAGUUUUCCCAAAACAAGUUCAUGGAAAGCUGUCUGGGACCUGUGAGUGUGCUGAUAAUCCCUAAUCCAAAGGCAUACCUUUGUUCCUACCUAUCACCCCAGUUCCCCUGCAAGUAGGAACCAUGUUAUAGAUCAAGAUGUAUAACUACGGACCUUAGACUAGAUGACUUAAAAUAACAAACCAGUACAUGCAGCCCCACCUUCUCAAGCUAUUUCCCAAGGAUUAGGGAUGCUGCUUUGGUUUUAAUGUUAUGAUUUCUGCCAGAUACAGUAGCUGUACACUUGGGAGCAUGAUGCUUUUUAAAGUUGCUAUUAUUUUUUAAAAAUUAGAAACAACUUAAACUAAUUUCCUUCCAAUUUUCUCCUAACCUCAGGUGAGGUACAAUAUGUAUCUCACAAAAACCAUUCAAUAUGUCUAGAAUACAAAUAGAAGGUACACUAUAAUUUGAGACAAUUUGCUGAUGUCAGGGUUAAUAGAAGUCUCUUUUCUUGGUUUGUCUUACCUUUAUUCAGUAUUUGGAAGCUUAAUGAAAUAUAAAGGUAAGUGCUGUGAACAAAUGUAAUCGCUGUUAUUGCUGUGGGAAUAUCUCAGAUUGCAUUGUAAUUUAAAGCUCUGGGACUUUAUAAACUGAUCAAGUUAUGUCAGAAACAAGUUUUAAGCUGUAGAAGCCUGAACUGAGAAUGAAUGCUCUAUUCCUGAGAAGCAAAAGCAAAUCCAAAGUUUCAUCUGUGUUAAAAGAUUGAUAAAAUUUUAAUAAAGAUGAAUAUCGCCUCUGGUACAUGGAGAAGCUGUGGGCCUGAAUGGGUGUAAGCUGGGCCUCAUAAAUAGGUGUUCUGUCUUUAUACUGAAAUAUUCUGUAAGAUUAAAUGAGAUAUAAUGUAUGUCAAGUGCCUAACACGUAGUUCCCUGGAAUCUAAUAGGCACUUUAAAAAUGCAAGUUCUCGGCCGGGCAUGGUGGCUUACAGCUGUAAUCCCAGCACUUUGGGAGGUCAAGGCAGGCAGAUCACUUGAGGUCAGGAGUUUGAGACCAGCCUGGCCAACAUGGUGAAAGCCCAUCUCUACUAAAGAUACAAAAAAUUAGCUGGGCGUGGUGGUGCACGCCUGUAAUCCCAGCUACUCGGGAGGCUGAGGCAAGCGAAUUGCUUGAACCCGGAAGGUGGAGGUUGCAGAGAGCCAAGAUCAUGCCAUUGCACUCCAGCCUAGGUGACAGUGUGACACUCCGUCUCAAAAAAAAGAAAAAAAAAUGCAAGUUAUCUCCUUCUUCUUUGCAUGCUGCUCACUUCUUAUACCCAGACAUUUAUGACUAUGUCAUUCAUAAAUUUGUCCAAACCUUUUGUGAAUUCCUUCUGUCAUAUCCUUCUGGUUUAAGAGAUGUGAGUCAUGCAAGAAAGAACAAAGAAUAAAAUUGAAAUGACAGUCUUACAGGUACAAUAAGAUAACAUUUUAAUGAAAAUUGCCAAAACUAGGCUACACAGUGUGAAGUCAUAUAAGUUCUGUGGCACAAUACACAGUUGCACACAAAUAUCCUUGUGGUCCUCUGAAAUCAGAUUAACAAAUGGUAGAUCAAAAAAUAUUUGCUGAGCACCCAUUAUGUGCCAGACACCAUGCUAAAUGUCUUAGGAGAUGCAAAGAGAGAAAUUCAUCCCCUACCUCAAGCAGCUAGGGAGGGAGGGUGGUGUAAGUGCUGGGGAGACAUGCAAAUGCACAGAUAGUUAUAAUACAGAGCAGAAAAAGAAUAAGACAGUAGGAAGAGUGACUGUGGAGAUGUGCAUCAAAUAUAAAGGGGAUACAAAGGAGUACAUAAAAUACCCUGCCCUCCAUGAGCUGAAAAUAUAAUCAAGAAAUCUAGUAGGUGAAAAGGUCAAGAUAAUGCAGUGGUCAGUUGCAGCCGGGCUGACCUCACUCUCUUCGCUCUCAGUCUUGGGCUUUAGUUCUUUCAUCUCCUAGGGUAAUAAUCCUCCUCCUCCAAAUGCCCGUUCCCUACUUCUCUAUUAUCUUCCUAGGUCCAGCUUCAAGUCCUGUGCCCUUCAAAAACCCUUACCUAAAUACAUCAAUCCCCUUUGAGCUCUUCCUUCACGUUCAUUUAUUCCUUGUUUCAUUUAACAAUUAUGUGUUGGGCCCCUACUAUUUGCCAGGCCUUAUUGAGACCUGGAUUCAGAGAUACAAAGACUAAUGAGAUAAUCCCAGUGCCCUCCAAAAUCUCACGAUCUAAUAAAGGUGACAGAACAAUGUGCUCACAUCCAGGACAGAUGAGGACCAUAGGGGAUAUGUUUCAACAAGACUUUGAACUGACUCUUAGAGGCUGAUUAGGAGUUCGCUAGGUGAAGAAGAAGAAAAAGGCAUUCUAGGCAGAGGGAACAAAGAUCAGAAAGGGACUGGUGCCUCAUGGGACCAGUGAAAAAUUUGCUAUGUGUAGAUUACAGGGUAUAUGAGAGACAGUAGGAAGGAUUAAGGCUUGAAUGGAAGUUAAGGCCAGAUUAUGAAGAGCCCUGAAUGCUACAUUAAAGAGCUUACACUUUUUUCUGUGAAAACAAAUGAGCUUUAACUUUUAAAAAGCUCAGUUGGUAGAGAUAGAUUGCAAAGAGGAGAGACUUGAGAAACGCAGACCUGUUAAGAGAUUCAAAUAUAUACCUAUAACACUUACAGUCUGUGCCAUUCAUUUGGUCAUCAUUGUUUUGGUUGUCUGCACCACGCCCCCAACCCUAGUGCUUAGCUGAGUGUUAAGUAGCCACCACCUAGUUGAAUAAAUGAGUGUUUGAGUAAGUGUCUCAAUAUUCAUAUUGGGAAACUUCUAUUUUUUUAAGAUGAAAGAAUUGGAAGCGUAAUCUAGCCUUUCUCUGGGAACCCAAUUUAACCUUAAUAGCAACUUUCCAUCCUUUGCAAGAGGUAUCAGGUAGCCCAGCUAUAGGAAACAGGUGUAUCCAUGGGAGAACAUUAUAUUACCAAUGCAGGGAAUGGAGUUCAGAAGGCAGAAGCCCAGCACAAAUAUUAGAAGUGAUAAGGGUAGGACUUCAAGUAUAGCGCUCAUAAAAUAUAAAACCGGUGAUACCAUAAAGCCAGUGAUGCCAUAAGGCCAGUGAUGGCAUAAAGCCAGUGAUGAGGAAGUUAGUUUCAGCCAGAGCACUGGGGAGCCAGGUUGGCCAGCCAAGCAGUCCCAGCUGGGAAAGCUGAGAAGAAUGGAGCUUGUAUGUAUGAUUGGCCCAGAUAUCUCUACCAUAGGGAAAGCCCAAAGGUGUCAUGGUACCAUGAAAAGACCAGUACAUGGCAAAUUUAGCACAAUCACAUGGAUUAUUAUGUAUAAAAAUGUUCUAUAGUCCAGUACUACUAUUUAGAUCCCGUGACUUAUCUAGGAUAGAGUAGGGCUGGGGUGUGUGUGUGUGUGUGUGUAUGUAUAUGUGUAUCAUCACAUAGGUUUACUAAUGGAAAAUAUUAACACUACUUAACCAGACUGCUUUUUAUGGACUGAUUAAACUGUACCUCAUUCAUAUUAGGGAACAUAUGUAGCCAUUAAAAAGAAUUAGGUCAAUUUAUAUACAAGUAUAUGUUACUAAUAAAAAAACAGCCUUCUUGCACUGUAACCUGUAGAUGGCACUGAAUCUAUAGAUUGAUUUGUGCAGGAGUAACAUCAUAACAAUAUUUAAUCUUUUAAGCCAUGAAUUUAUCUUUCUAUUUACUUGAGUCUUCUUUAAUUCCAAAUUAUAAUCUGUACUCUCCAGUAAACACAUCUUACACAAAUAUUAUUGAAUUUAUCCCUAAGUACUGUAUUUCAUUAUUUUGAUCCUAUGUAAAUGGUAUUUUCAUUUCAAUUUCCAAUAGUUUGUUGCCAGAAUAUUGAAGGACAAUUGACUUUUCAUAUUGAUCUUGAAUAAUGUAACCUUGCUAAAUUUACUUAUUAGCUCUAGUAACUUUUUUGUAGAUUGCUUAGCAUAAUCCAUGUAUGCAAACAUCAUCUGUGAAUAAAGAGAAUUUUCUUUCUGUAUAA